AGUCCUGAGGUCAUUUUGGGUGUCUGUAGGGUGAGGAUGGGGCAGGACAUGGGGAGGGAGAACUUAGGGCUGCCUCUGGUUUCUCAGGGCAGCCUUAAAAAAAAACUAUAGUGGCCAAGUGUAGUGGCUCAGGUAACCUUAGCUCUUUGGGAGGCUGAGGUGGGAGGAUUGCUUGAGGCUAGGAGUUUGAGAUUGGCCUGGACAACAUAGUGAGACCUGCCCCCGCCCCCCUCCCCCCAAAAAAACCCCAAAAAACUGUAGUAGUGUUGAGUAGGUGAUGUCUUUACUUUUUUUUUUUUUAUGUUUUUUAGACGGAGUUUUGCUCUUGUUGCCCAGGCUAGAGUGCAAUGGCAUGAUCUCAGCUCACUGCAACCUCCGCCUCCUGGGUUCAAACAAUUCACCUGCCUCAGCUUCCCGAGUAGCUGGGAUUACAGGCAUGUGUCACCAUACCCAGCUAAUUUUGUAUUUUUAGUAGAGACAGGGUUUCUUCUCCAUGUUGGUCAGGCUGGUCUUGAACUCGCGACUUCAGGUGAUCUGCCCGCUUUGGCCUCCCAAAGCCCUGGGAUUACAGACGUGAGCCACCACGCCCAGCCUUUUUUUUUUUUGGAGAUGGAGUCUCACUCUGUUGCCCAGGCUGGAAUGCAGUGGCACAAUCUUGGCUCACUGUAACCUCCGCUUCCCAGAUUCAAGCGAUUCUCCUGCCCCAGCCUCCCAAGUAGCUGCGAUUACAGGCGUGCGCCACCAUGCCGGGCUAAUAUUUUUUUUUUUUUUUUUUUUGAGACAGUCUCACUUUGUCACCAGGCUGGAGGGCAGUGGCAUGUUCUUGGCUCACUGCAACUUCUGCUUCCUCGGUUCAAGCAAUUCUCCUGCCUCAGCCUCCCAAGUAGCUGGGACUACAGGCACAUGCCACCACGCCUAGCUAAUUUUUGUAUUUUUGGUAGAGACAGGGUAUCACCAUGUUGGCCAGGAUGGUCUUGAUCCCUUGACCUCGUGAUCCACCCACCUUGGCCUCCCCCAAAGUUGGAAUUGCAGGCAUGAGCCACCACGCCCGGCCGACUUUACAUUUUAAGAGCAUAAAACUACUUUUCCCUGUAUGGUUUUUUUUCCCCCCCAAGAGACAUGGUUUUGCUCUGUCACCCAGGCUAGAGUGCAGAGGCUCAUGAUCACAAUCACUAUAGCCUCGACCUCCUGGACUUAAGCCAUCCUCCCACCUUAGUCUCCUAAAGCACUGGGAUUACAGGUCCCCAUCUAUUAUAAGAUGUAAUUGCACUUAAUUUGUAGACAUCCUUCAAGUGAUAUGUGGGUGACCAUUUAAAGAUACAAAAAAGGAGCACAUGGAAAUGGGAGGAGCCAACUAAAUAUCAGGUCCUGCACUGGGCUCCAGUGGUUGACUGUGUUAGUCCCGGGCAAGAGCGAGGGCCUUAACACUGCCAAGGAUGCUGGAUGAGACCUGGUUAAGGAAAUUGAACAUGUUUUGUUCAGAUGAGAGAUGAUUUGGGGUGGGGGUGGUGGCAGGUUCCGGAAGGCCCCAGGAUCUUGGCUCAAGACUGGACUGAAGGCCUUUCCUGAUGCUGGCACCAGGCAGGCUUGCUCACUCCCUUGGGAAAUACAGAGGGGGUUACUCUUACUUUCCAGAGAUGAGAUCAGGUGACCCUAUUGCAAAAGGCAGCAGAAGUGGACAGUGGCUACCUGGGGAAGGAGCUCAGCAUUGAGUGAGCAGCUCAGAAUCUUACACUCACCUUCUAUGAAGUUUAAGAUGAAGGGAGCUGCUCUACUCUGUUGCCUUGGUUUAUUGCAUUAGGGAAAAGAAUACUUAAAUUGCUUGGAAAAAUUGGAGUAGUUUUGAGCUGUUUAGCCAGUCUUCUGAGUUUGUAAACUACUCUUGGUUGUUUUUUUUUUUAAACUUUUUUUUUGUUUUGAGGCGGAGUUUCGCUCUUGUUGCCCAGGCCAGAGUGCAAUGGCUCUAUCUUGGCUCACUGCAACCUUGUCUCCAGGGUCCAAGCGAUUCUCCUGCCUCAACCUCCCAAGUAGCUGGGAUUACAGGCAUGCACCACCAUGCCUGGCUAAUUUUUGUAUUUUUAGUAGAGACAGGGUUUCACCAUGUUGGCCAGGCUGGUCUCGAACUUCUGACCUCUGGUAAUCUGCCUGCCUCGGCCUCCCAAAGUGCUGGGAUUACAGGUGUGAGCCACCGUGCCCGGCCUAAAACUUAUUUUUUAAAGUUAAUCCGUUGACAUUUUAGAGCUUAAGCUGCUUCGGCAGAUACCCUGUGGAAUGAAAUGCAGCUGGGCUUUGCAUCACCACACAGUGAAGUGACUGGUGUAGGAGAUGUGUUGCUGGCUGUAGGAUUCUCUAAGCAGAGCUUCUUAGUUGGUGGGCUGGGAUGAGUGACAGGGGUGCAGACGUCCUUGUGGGUAAGUGGCCCCUGCCCUUGACCAGCUCCUUAGGCUGAGAAUAGCCUCAUCUUACUCCAGUGUCUUCCACACUUAGAAUUCUUACUACAUGGCAGAAGCUGAAAAAGAUGGGGCAUCUGAUUACCCCCCCACCCACUAUUCUGAGAAGAGAGAUGAUUUUUCUUGGCUCUCUCAGUCUCAGGGUAUCCACAGCUCCUGUGGAGAAGGGGUUCCUCUGCACGCUGCACUAGAGGAGUGUUGGGUGCGGGGGGUGGAGUUGGCCAUUCACCCUCCUGGACCUCAGGAUUUAUGGAAAGUCAUACUGGGAACUAAGGGCGAAAGCACAGGUUGCUGUGGUUAUUGUUGAUGUCCUGAAACAGGAGACUGUUCAUACUUCACUCUCAAAAUAUGGAGAGCCCUCAGAGGUUUCUGAGCAUGACAAUAUCGACUUGAAUUGGGCAGAAGAAAGGCCAUUGAUAAAAGGCAGGCAUGAGCUAAUAUGGCCUUGGAUUUGCCUGACGGAAUAAAAAGCAGGGACAGGUGCCAGAGACACUGCAGGAAGAUUGGGUAGGGAUUAACUGGAUACCAAGGGCUGAGGACAGUUCAUCUGUUUGACAACUGUUGGAGUGCCUUCCCUGCUCGACCAGUGCUGAGCCCCAGGGGUGUCUGGUUGUGAGGGAGAUUCCUGCCUUCCGGGGUCUUAGAGCCUCGUGGGGGAAACAGGGCAGGGUGUCAUGAUGCAGACAUCUGGGGCACUCAGCUAAAGGGCGGGCAGGAGCGGUGUCGUAGCAGUGGCAGCUGAAUGACGACUGGAGGGUGACAUAGGCCCUCAGAUUGUGGAUCUUUGGUUUUAGGGGUAGUGAGCUAGGUCCUGGAGGGUGCUCUGGGACAGCUGGGUAUUGGCCCUGGGCAGUCAUUGUCAGCUGUGAUGGCCGAGGAUGCAGUGGGUGAGGUGUGGAGGCCCCAUGUGACCAUCAGGACCUUCAUGAAUGAAGAGAGCAUGGCUCUCUGACCCCAUCUGACUGGCCAGCUCCAGGGGCAGGUGUAGAAUUUGAUCCGUCCUCGUGUGUCCCCCUCUCCAAACUGUAGUGCUUUGUGUUAGGUGAAAGUGUGACAAGUAAUAGUUGAAAGAAUGAAAUAUCCAAGGGACCAUCUCCAUACAUUGGAAAAGUUUGUUCUGCUCUGUUCCUAUGAAUGAAAUAGCAGCAGAUGGAUGGAAGUUCGAGGAACACAGACUUGACUUAGCCUGAGAAAGAUCUUUGUAGCAGUUGGAGGUAUCGGGAAGAGGCUCAGUGUGAACCCAGAGCCCUGGGAGCUGGUUGGGAACCCACAUUUUCUAGAUUUCUGAGGAUUUUCCAGCUUGAGGUUUUGGACACUUUUCCAGAAAGACCCAGAGCGAUUAAGACACGUCUCUGAAACAACCACAUGAAUUAUUCUAACAGCUGCUGCUUGCUGGUUUUAGGAAGUUUCCUUGUUUCAUGCACUGCUCAAAUGUUUUCAGAUUCUAGCUCUUUUGGCAGAGUUUGGGGGAGAAGACAGGUGGGUGUCCCGCUGUGACACUGGUUUUGAGAGUGGGGAGGGGUUGUGGUCGCCGGAAGGAAAAGAGCCCUGGGGAUUUGCCACUUGGGUAAAAAUGACUUGGUAUCUGACUAGUAAUCACCAAGACCCAAACAGGGUCAUUUUGGGGUGGAAGUGAAGUAUCAGAUGAGUUAGGUGGGAGUGGGCUGGGAUGUACUCUGGCUACUGCCCACUCCAAAAGGCCUCCUAGCUGGGCCUGGGCUGUCUCUCAGGGCCUGUACCCUCCACCAUCCUUGAAUUCAGUGGCCAGGGAACCCGUCCCCUCCCCCUGGUCUGUGCCUGCUCUGCUCAUUGCCUCACAUGUGUGAGCACUCGGUGGAAGGAGGAAGGGAUGUCUGCACACACUCCCUGUCGAGGGACCCUGGCUUGCUCCUGUGGUGCCCUAAGCAUGUAGUUGGCAUGCAUGUGUGUCACAAUGAAAAUGAAGAUGAGAAUUGGUCCUAGUUUAUGACCCAGGCCGGGUAGUAUUUGUCGAUCCUUCCAGCCCCUUCCUGCAUCUCGUACACUGGCAGACAGGGACUCAGAGGCCAGGUGGCUGUUCCUGCCCAUGGAACUCUGAGGGUUUCCAUGCCUUCUACAGCUGGGCUCAGUCCUGGGAGUUUCUAGCAAUUCAGUAGAGGGUUAGGUUAACGUGCACUUAGAGGAAUAGAGGAAUCCUGGGUCUGUAAUGAUCUCUACAUCUUUUUUUUUUUUUUUUUUUUUUUUAAGAUGGAGUCUUGUUCUGUCACCCAGGCUGGAGUGCAGUGGUGCAAUCUCAGUUCACUGCAGCCUCCGCCUCCCAGGUUCAGGUGAUUGUUGUGCCUCAGCUGCUCGAAUAGCUGGGAUUACAGGCACAAGCCACCAUGCCCAGCUAAUUUUUGUAUUUUAGUAGAGAUGGGGUUUUGCCAUGUUGGCCAGGCUGGUCUUGAACUCCUGACCUCAGGUGAUCCGCCUGCCUUGGCCUCCCAAAGUGCUGAGACAGGUGUAAGUCACCGCCCUGGAUGAUGCCUACCUACAUCUUUGGUAGAGGAAGUUUUCCCAGAGCCUUGGGAAGGAUCCAGUCCUAGGACCGUCUCAAUCAGAUUGUUCUCAAUGGUACAGCGGUUCAGGUUUGAGCCUGGGCCUAGGAGGUGGCUGACCUGGGUCUGGAUUCCCAUCUGACUUAUUAAGUGUGUGACCUUGGGCAACCAUCUUGACUUUUUUUUUUUUUUUUUUUUUUUGAGACAGAGUCUCACUCUGUCACCCAGGCUGGAGUGCAGUGGUGUGAUCUCAGCUCACUGCAACCUCUACUUCCCAGGUUCAAGCGAUUCUCCUGUCUCAGCCCCCUGAGUAGCUGGGAUUAUAGGCACGCACCACUAUAUCCAGCUAGUUUUUUUUUUUUUUUUUUUUUUUUAAGUAGAGACGGGGUUUCACCAUGUUGGCCAGGCUGGUCUCGAACUCCUGACCUCAGGUGAUCCGCCCGCCUCGGCCUCCCAAAGUGCUGGGAUUACAGGCGAGAGCCGUCGCGCCCAGCCCAUCUUGACUUUUUUUUUUUUUUUUUUGAUACGGGGUCUCGCUCUGUCACCCAGGCUGGAGUGCAGUGGCGCGAUCUCGGCUCACUGGAAGCUCUGCCUCCCAGGUUCCCGCCAUUCUCCUGCCUCAGCCUCCCAAGUAGCUGGGACUACAGGCGCCCGCCACCACGCCUGGCCAAUUUUUUUUUUUUUUGGUAUUUUUAGUAGAGAUGGGGUUUCACUGUGUUAGCCAGGCUGAUCUCGAUCUCCUGACCUCGUGAUCCGCCCGCCUUGGCCUCCGAAAGUGCUGGGAUUACAGGUGUGAGCCACCGCGACCAGCCCCAUCUUGACUUUUUUUAACCUCGGUUUUCUCUUCUGUCAGGUGUGGAUAUCGGCGGUAGUCCCUUGCAUGAAGUGCUGAUAACAGUGUGGGUUCCAUCGUGUGAAGUGUGGGUACGAUGACAGUCCCUCGUGUGAGUGUGGGUAUGAUGACAGUCCCUCGUAUGAGUGUUGGUAUGAUGACAGUACCUCGUUCUGUGGUUAUGAGGAUUAAAUGAAAUCAGGCAUGUAACGUGUUGGCACAUUGCCUGGCACCAAAUAAAGAAUUCAGUAAUUGUUAGCCACUGUUUCCUCUUUCAGUAACAAAACCUCUUGUCAACAUAUUAGAGAUGAUUCUCUUGGUGUCCCCAAAGUUUUCAGAAGUGCGCUUUUCUCUAGCAGUUUGAAUCCAGGUGCCUAGCGGUAACUUUCUCCGUUGAGGGUCAGGUCCUCCCCAUCCUGCCUCAGCAAUGCCCGACGGACAAUGGGGGAGGCCUGGACUGUGAGGAUGCACGAGCAGUCCCAUUCUGGGGACAGAGACAAGCAGGGCCUGGCUUGGCUGCAUGUUAGUGCUGGCAUAGGGGUUAGGUAGGGUCUGGAUCUGCUUGAGGUGGCUUGAGAUAGAGGGAGGGAGGGCCAGGGAGGUGAGGGCAGUAGGCCUCCUUGGAGGAAGAGAAGGCUGGCCCAGUGAAAGCCAGUUGAAUGGAUGAGUGAACUAACGCCCCUGCCCCUAUGGCCCUGCCCCUCCUCACCCCUUCUGGCCUGUACUGUCCCUUCGCCUGUCCAUACCAGUUUCCCAGGGCAUGUCUUGCAUGUAGGUUGGGUUGUCUAGGCAGCGCUGUGCUUCAGUGACACUUUGUGGUUGACUUGGGACCCUGACCACACUGAGAGCAGCGCGCUUCUCUGGGUUGGAUGGCUGGGUUCUCAAGGACCAACGGCUUAGAAUUGUGGAGGGUGGAGUGUGUCCCGGCCCUGUGUUUGUUUGCCUGCCUGCUGACAUGAAGCCUGAUGUGUGCAGCCACUCUACUGUGUGCGAGGGAAGAAAGACAUCCUAGUCCGUGUUGGACAUGGGCUCUGUGUGGCAGAGUUCAGCCUCUUGUGGGGCCCCGUCUUACUCUGGGGGUGAUGCAGGUAAAGUCUGCUGAGGACCUAGCCUAAGGCUGUGUAGUCUGACAGAUUUCUUCAGACCUUCUCUCUCUUUUUUUUUUUUCUUCUUUUUUGAGACAGAGUCUCACUCUGUUGCCCAGGCUGGGAGUGUGCAGUGGUGCAAUCUUGGCUCACUGCAACCUCCACCCCCUGGGUUCAAGCAGUUCUCCUGCCCCAGCCUCCCACGUAGCUGGGAUUACAGGCUCCCACCACCAUGCCCAGCUAAUUUUUGUAUUUUUGGUAAAGACUAGGGUUUCACCAUGUUGGCUAGGCUGAUUUCGAACUCCUAACUUCAGGUGAUCUGUCCUCCUUGGCCUCCCAAAGUGCUGGGAUUACAGGCGUGAGCCACUGCACCCAGCCAGACCUUCUUAUUUUUAGGCAGUGAUUCUAGUGAAAUUUACAUUGUUCUUUAUAACAUAUCAGCAUUUUCAUACUGAAGCCUCUUCCCAGCAAGGAAAACGCCAUUUGAGGCAGAAACAGCAAGCAUAUUUCAAGGCUCUGGGAUUGCUUGCUUCCCACCGCAGGAGGCAGGCGGUUUGGCCUUUGCUAUCUGGCUCCUCUUGGAGCAGGGUUCCCCAGGUGCCAGCCCCCACCAGCACAGUUUUUCUCUCUGCUUGCUCCCUGGAAGCUGGCUGUUGGGCCACACAAGCAGAACUCCUCCUAGCUGGCAGAGCCCCACGUCCACCUGGCACCUGCUUUCCCCAAGCCUCGGUGUCCCUUCUGUGACAUCUAAGACUUCAGGGAGGCAUUGCUUCCUCCAUCUUGGCCUCAGUUUAUCCUGUAAGGGCUGGGGAUAGUGGUGAGGACAGUUGACAGUUCUGUGAAACACUCUGAGGAGCCCUUGCUCUUCUUGCAUCUUCCAAUCAUACUUUUAUUGUCUGAUACUAUACAUUGUCAAGGAGGUGUGGAGUAUGUGUACAGCCUUGCAUUUCUCUAUUCUUUUUGUUUUUGUUGUUUUUUUUUUUUUGAGAUGGAGUCUGGCUCUGUCACCCAGGCUGGAGUGCAGUGACGCGAUCUUGGCUCACUGCAAGCUCCGCCUCCCGGGUUCAUGCCACUCUUCUGCCUCAGCCUCCCAAGUAGCUGGGACUACAGGCGCCCACCACCACGCCCGGCUAAUUUUUUGUAUUUUUAGUAGAGACAGGGUUUCACCGUUUUAGCCAGGAUGGUCUCGAUCUCCUGAACUCAUGAUCUGCCCGCCUCGGCCUCCUGAAGUGCUGGGAUUACAGGCGUGAGCCACUGCGCCCGGCCUUUUGUUUGUUUUUGAGUUAGGAUUUCGUUCUGUCAUCCAGGCUGGCGUGCAGUGGCACAAAAAUGGCUCACUGGAGCCUUGACUUCCUGGACUCAAGUGAUCUUCCCACCUCAACCUCCCGAGUGGCUGGGAUUGCAGGUGCGCACCACCACUCCCAGCUAAUUUGAAAAUAUUUUGUAGAGACAGAGUCCCAUUGUAUUGCCUAGGCUGGUCUCAAACGCCUGGGCUCAAAGCAGUCCUCCUGUCUGUCUCCCAAAGUGCUGAGGUUACAGGCAUGAGCCACCACACUUGGCCUAUUUCUCUCUUAAUUGGCGUAUGCGGUGGCGGCUGAGAUUUGCUGAUAGAUUUUGCCAUUGUUAUAGUUUCUUCAUUUAUACUUUGCAGCAUUUCAGUCAUCACAUGAUUUUUGUGAUGGCUGUGGUGCGUCAUCAGUUUGCCGCAGUGAUGAAGCUUCUGGGACUAAGAACCAGCUUGUUGGCCUGGUUCUUGGGCAAGGCCCUGAGAAUCCUGGGCUGAAUGCCCCCCUGAGCUGACCACGUGGCCUUAGCCAGGGCCAUUGGUGCCAUGGCGUGGUUAGUGGAUGGUUCCAGCCAAGUCUGAGAAUUUACCGAAUUGACUGUUUGAUUUGGCAGCUGAUGGUCAGAGAAAUUGAAUUCUGCCUCUUAGCAAAGGAAGCUUGGUGGAUUUCUAGAAUUCUUUGUUGUAGAGGGGGUUGGGGAUGGCGUGGGCAGAAUGAAUGCGAAGUGUGGGGGCUUGAGGUCUGCCAGGCCCUCCCACUUGCCCUAAACUGGACUUGGAGGUGUCUGGAAGGUUGUGGGUGGACAGCACUGACCUUGCUGCUUGGCCAGUUGUUCCCCAGCCACUCUGGAUUCGGAUCUAGGUGGACCCUAUGGUAUCCUAGAAACUACCUUUAUGUUCUUUUCUUUUAAGAAACAGUGUCUUGCUCUGUCAUCCUGGCUGGAGUGUAGUUGCAUGAUCAUGGGUCACUGUAACAUUUAAACUCCAGGGCUCAAGUGAUCCUUCCACCUCAGCCUCCCGAGUAACUUGGGACUACAGGUAUGCACCACCACACCCAGCUAGUUUUUAAAUUUUUUAUAGAAACAGGGUCUCACUGUUUUCUAGGGCUGGUCUUAAACUCUUGGGCUCAAGUGAUCCUCCCACCUCAGCGUCCCAAAGGGCUGGGAUUACAGGCAUGAGCCACUGCAUGUGGCUUUGUAAGUUUUUGUUGUUGUUUUUGAUACAGGGUCUUGCUCUGUCGUCCAGGCUAGAGUGCAGUGGCGUGAUAUUGGCUCACUGUAUCCUCCACCUCCCAGGCUCAAGUGAUUCUCCUGCUUCAGCGUCCUGAGUAGCUGUGACCAUAGGCAUGAGCCAGCAUGCCCAGCUAAUUUUUGUAUUUUUUGUAAAGACGGAGUUUUGCUAUUUUGCCCAGGCUGGUCUUGAACUCCUGAGAUCAAGAGGUCUGCCCCCCUCAGCCUCCCAAAGCGCUGGGAUUACAGGUGUGAGACACUGCGCCUGACCUCCACUGAGUUUUUAAAUUUUUUGUAGAGAUGGGGGUCUCUCUCUGUUGCUCAGGCUGGUCUCGAACUCCUGGCCUCAAGUGAUCCUCCUGCCUCGGCCUCCCAAAAUGCUGGGAUUACAGGCAUGAGCCAUCAUGCCUGGCCUGGCGCUUUACUUUUGACCAUGUGACACACCUGUGGUUGGGGUCUGGGGCCUCAGAGGCAGCGACUGUGCUGUGCAUUGGUGAAGGAAGCAUCCUCACCUUUCCAGGAGGUUGCCCAUAUGACAGGUUAGGUGUUGUUCCUGCUUGAAAAACAAACUUGAGCUGGGUGUGGUGGCUUGUGCCUGUAAUCCCAGCACUUUGGGAGGCUGAGGCAGGAUGAUUACUUGAAGCUAGGAGUUUGAGACCAUCCUGGGCAACAUAGUGAGAUCCCAUCUCUACAAAAAAUAAAAAAGGUGUGGUGCAGUCAUUGACACCUAUAAUCCCAGCCCUUUUGGAGGCCAAAGUAGGAGGAUUGCUUGAGGCCAAGAGUUCAAGACUAGCCUGUGCAACAAUAAAAAAAAAAAAAAAACCCAAACUUGAGAAAACUUGCCAUAAGAAUAGAAUAACUGGAGGUUUUAUUUCUUGGCAUUAAGUGAACAAAACCCAGCCACUGACCGUAAAGGUAAUACAAUUAGUUGAAAUAUUGCAGUGUGGGGAGGCUAUUUGGGUGGCAAUUUGUUGGGGACAAGGCUGGCUGUCAUUAGAACCUUCUGUGUGCAUUCUCCUAUGAUGGAGGCAGUGUCUUCUGCCAGAUGGAGCCUUUUGGGAUCCUCCCAAAUUUUUUUAUUUUGACUGGUCCUGGCCAUUCGGCUGUUCCCUCCCCUCCCCUUUAUUAGAGUCAUCCCAAGAGGACUCUGUGCUUUGUGGUCACAGGUCACACAGGUGCAUGUGCAAAGGAGAUGGCCUGUUUAGAGGUGAAUGAGGUGGGAGCACCAGAUAGUUGUUUACCCCCUUUCCCCUUACUCUAUUCAGGAGCACUUGACCAAGCCAUAAUUAGCAUGCUUUGCACAUUUCCAAUCUGAAAUGAUUGGCAAAGAAAUGCCCGCUCUCUUGUUCCAGUUGGGUACCUCAGGCGGGGUCACUGGGCAUUUUGUUUUUCACCCAGCAUCUGUGGACUCAGCCACACACCGGCCUGGCAGACAGCUCCCCAGUGCAGCAACUCCCAUGGGCCCAAGGGAUUAUAGGCAGGCUUGGAGCUCAGAACUUGACAGGGGACAUAGUGGUUUUCUUUUUCUUUUCUUUUCUUUUUUUUUUUUUAGACAAGGUCUGGCUCUGUCGCCCAGGCUGGACUGCAGUGGCUCAGUGUCUGCUCACUGCAUCCUCCACCUCCUGGGCUUAAGGCAUCUUCCCAUGUCAGCCUCUAGCGUAGCUGGGACUACAGGUGCUCCGCCACGCCUGGCUAAUUUUUGUAUUUUUUGUAGGGAUGGUGUUUUGCUAUGUUGUCCAGGCUGGUCUCGAACUUGUAAGCUCACGCAAUCCAUCCACCUCGGCCUCCCAAAGUGCUGGGAUUACAGGCAUGAACCACUGCACCUGGCCCCUGCAGACAUAGUGGUUUUCUUUUUAAUGAUGUUAAUUAGUAGGGGCACUAUGGGUGGGUUGUCUGGAGUUUCCCUUGUCUAGAGUUAGAUGUGAUGGGAGCUCAGGGCUCAUACCCAGCCGUGGGUCCAUAUAAGUCUUCGUGUGUCUAGCUUGGGUGCUCCAGGAAGUGUAUUUGGGAUGUCUCUGGCUUCUAUUCCACAAACUUAGAGGAGAAGUUUGUACCCAAGAUGAGCUAGUCAUCUCCAUUCACACAACAAGCAUUCCUUGGCUUAUGGCUGUGAGACAAGGCUAGAGUCCCCGGGAGGUACUGUUCUUCUGCAGCUAAGAGCUGGGAUCAGGCCGGCAGACUUGUCCAUCUAUGACAUAAUGUGUGGCCGCUGCUGUUACCUCACCAUUCCAUGUGUUUCCAGUGCUUUUUAAUUUAAUUUUUAUUUUUUUGAGAUAGAAUCUUGCUCUUUUGCCCAGGCUGGAAUACAGAGAUGCGAUCUUGGCUCACUGCAGCCUCCGCCUCCUGGGUUCCAGUGAUUCUUGUGCCUCAGCCUCCCGAGUAGCUGAGACUACAGGCACACACCCCUACCCCUGGCAAAUUUUUUUUGUAUUUUUAAUGGAGAUGGGGUUUCACCAUGUUGCACAGGCAGGUCUCGAACUUCUGGCCGCAAGCGAUCCACCCGCCUCAACCUCCCAAAGUGCUGGGAUUACAGGCGUGAGCCACUGCCCCCGGCCUCCAGUGCUUUCUUUAUGCGGCUUAUUUGAGAAGCGGAGGGAAGGACUAGUUGGUAGUGAAGCAUGUCAGUGGCAUGGCUGAGCUGGGGAGCAGAGUUUCAGAACCAUGCUUUGUUUGGCACCAUGGGUAUACCAGGCUCAUGUGCUUUUUUUCUGUACACGCUUUGGCAUGUGAUGUGUGUGGCUCUGCCUUGAGGACAUUAUGCUGAGUAAGAGAAGUCAGGCUCAAAAAGACACACUUAUGAUUGCACCUAUAUGAGGUUCCUAGACUCUCAAAUUCUUAAAGACAGAAGGAAGAAGGGGGGUUGCCAGGGGUUGGGGGCAGAGAGAUGAGAGUGAGUAUUUAAUGGGGAUAGAGUUUCAGCUGGGGAAGAUGGUAAGUUCUGGAGAUGGAUGGAUGAUGGUUGCACAACAGUGUGACUGCACCUAAUGCCACUGAACUGUGAACUCAAAAUGGUUAAGAUGUAAAUUUUGUGUACGUUUUACCACAAUAAAAAAAUGAACCUUUCUGAAUUCAGAAAUAUUCUAUACCUUUAUGACAACAUGUAUUCUGUCCUCUCAGAAUUAGCUUGGGGACAAAGGGACAAAGGCACACACACUCAUUUCCUAGCUUGUGCUAAGUACUGGGGGUGGGGGUGGGGUUAAAAAAAUGCACGUGGUUCUAGAAGGCUCUUAAUGACAUCAUCUUGGGAUCACAAUGUUAGAGUGCGGAUAUUCUAUGGGUUUUCUUCAGUCCCUGGACAGGUGGGGUCAUCCUAGGACCCCUGCAAUCUUUAGGGGAUUUAGGGAGAAACAGUGUCCAGGAACAUCUGAGGUCUCUGUUCCCGUGCAUUGCUUGGGGAUUGAAGGAGCAACAGAUUUGGAUGAAACCCUGAGGAUCCCAGAGCUGAAAGUGAGUUUGAAGUGUCCGAUCCAGUCCUUCAACUCAGAGCACUCCUAUCUGUGACACCUCUGCCCACGCAUCCAGUAUGUGCAGCACACCUGCUCUGUGACUGACACUCUUGCAGAAGUGGGGCCACUUCAGGGACAUGGACAAGGUGUUGUACCUGCUGUCACAGAGCCUGUUAUCUGUUCAGAAUGACCGAAGAAGCAUGCCGAACACGGAGUCAGAAACGAGCGCUUGAACGGGACCCAACAGAGGACGAUGUGGAGAGCAAGAAAAUAAAAAUGGAGAGAGGAUUGUUGGCUUCAGAUUUAAACACUGACGGAGACAUGAGGGUGACACCUGAGCCGGGAGCAGGUCCAACCCAAGGAUUGCUGAGGGCAACAGAGGCCACGGCCAUGGCCAUGGGCAGAGGCGAAGGGCUGGUGGGCGAUGGGCCCGUGGACAUGCGCACCUCACACAGUGACAUGAAGUCCGAGAGGAGACCCCCCUCACCUGACGUGAUUGUGCUCUCCGACAACGAGCAGCCCUCGAGCCCGAGAGUGAAUGGGCUGACCACGGUGGCCUUGAAGGAGACUAGCACCGAGGCCCUCAUGAAAAGCAGUCCUGAAGAACGAGAAAGGAUGAUCAAGCAGCUGAAGGAAGAAUUGAGGUUAGAAGAAGCAAAACUCGUGUUGUUGAAAAAGUUGCGGCAGAGUCAAAUACAAAAGGAAGCCACCGCCCAGAAGCCCACAGGUUCUGUUGGGAGCACCGUGACCACCCCUCCCCCGCUUGUUCGGGGCACUCAGAACAUUCCUGCUGGCAAGCCAUCACUCCAGACCUCUUCAGCUCGGAUGCCCGGCAGUGUCAUACCCCCGCCCCUGGUCCGAGGUGGGCAGCAGGCGUCCUCGAAGCUGGGGCCACAGGCGAGCUCACAGGUCGUCAUGCCCCCACUCGUCAGGGGGGCUCAGCAAAUCCACAGCAUUAGGCAACAUUCCAGCACAGGGCCACCGCCCCUCCUCCUGGCCCCCCGGGCGUCGGUGCCCAGUGUGCAGAUUCAGGGACAGAGGAUCAUCCAGCAGGGCCUCAUCCGCGUCGCCAAUGUUCCCAACACCAGCCUGCUCGUCAACAUCCCACAGCCCACCCCAGCAUCACUGAAGGGGACAACAGCCACCUCCGCUCAGGCCAACUCCACCCCCACUAGUGUGGCCUCUGUGGUCACCUCUGCCGAGUCUCCAGCAAGCCGACAGGCGGCCGCCAAGCUGGCGCUGCGCAAACAGCUGGAGAAGACGCUACUCGAGAUCCCCCCACCCAAGCCCCCAGCCCCAGAGAUGAACUUCCUGCCCAGCGCCGCCAACAACGAGUUCAUCUACCUGGUCGGCCUGGAGGAGGUGGUGCAGAACCUACUGGAGACACAAGCAGGCAGGAUGUCGGCCGCCACUGUGCUGUCCCGGGAGCCCUACAUGUGUGCACAGUGCAAGACGGACUUCACGUGCCGCUGGCGGGAGGAGAAGAGCGGCGCCAUCAUGUGUGAGAACUGCAUGACAACCAACCAGAAGAAGGCGCUCAAGGUGGAGCACACCAGCCGGCUGAAGGCCGCCUUUGUGAAGGCGCUGCAGCAGGAACAGGAGAUUGAGCAGCGGCUCCUGCAGCAGGGCACGGCCCCUGCACAGGCCAAGGCCGAGCCCACCGCUGCCCCACACCCCGUGCUGAAGCAGGUCAUAAAACCCCGGCGUAAGUUGGCGUUCCGCUCAGGAGAGGCCCGCGACUGGAGUAACGGGGCUGUGCUACAGGCCUCCAGCCAGCUGUCCCGGGGUUCGGCCACGACGCCCCGAGGUGUCCUGCACACGUUCAGUCCGUCACCCAAACUGCAGAACUCAGCCUCGGCCACAGCCCUGGUCAGCAGGACCGGCAGACAUUCUGAGAGAACCGUGAGCGCCGGCAAGGGCAGCGCCACCUCCAACUGGAAGAAGACGCCCCUCAGCACAGGCGGGACCCUUGCGUUUGUCAGCCCAAGCCUGGCGGUGCACAAGAGCUCCUCGGCCGUGGACCGCCAGCGAGAGUACCUCCUGGACAUGAUCCCACCCCGCUCCAUCCCCCAGUCAGCCACGUGGAAAUAGUGCGAGCCAGGCCCCGUGGAAGACGGGCUCCCUCCUCCCCCACCUGGCCCCUGGUCUAGAAGGACCCACUGCACCACCCUCCGCUGGCUCGGGAAGACACCGUGCCCGCCCCAAGAGCAAGCACCGGCCAUGCUGCAGAGGCAAGACCUCAAUUCUUGGCUGCAAAGUUUCAUCAGGGCUAGGGGGCUGGUGCCGCCUCAUAGGCAGACGAGGAUCAUCGCUGGGGGACCUUUCCCGUGGGCUUUCUUCCUUUCUCUCUUUGCCUUUAGUUUGCCCGACACCAGCAGAAAAGUGGACCUUGGGGGCUGGUUCUGCUCCUGGCCCCCUUGUUCAGCCCCUGCCGGCACACGGGCGGCUCACCCUGGACACUGUGAUGCGCAUGGGCAAGGCCAGCGCCCGGGGCUUCUGAACCGAGCGGGGUGUUUCAUUUUUUUGCUUUUCCCUGUCUUAGGCUCCCAGUCUUUGACUGCCUUCCCAUGGCGAUCUAUAAGUUGAAAGAUUUUUUUUUUUUUUAAUCACCUCAUGAUGAUGGAGUUAAAAGUAAACCGUGCAGACCCUGGGGUCCCUGUUGUACGCUGCAUCAUCCCGCUGGCCCUGUGCCCUGGAGGGUGGGCGGCUCAUGGUGCCACAGCCCCUGGCAGGGACGGCCGGCCCGCCCCCGUGACUGACUGACAGAUGCAGGGAUGGCCGAGGCAGCCCUCGCUCCAGCUGAACGCCUCCAUUGCUGCUUGUUCUGGAGACCCCCGCCCCCGCACCUUCCAGACUUAGCAGAAGAACAAACUGAAGAACAGACCCAGCCAGAGAAGCAGGGAUUCCAGAAGCUGCCCAUUAAGGGAGAAGGAGAGGAUCCGGUCGGCAGCAGCCCUGAGCAGAAAGCUGGAGGGGGGACUGUCGCGGGGUUUUUCUGUUGUGGUUUAUUUUAUUAAAUUUUUUCCUUUUUUCUAUUCAUUUCGAUGGACGCAAUCUUAAGCCACCCUGGCCUUGCUCCUGGGAGGUGAGCGUGCACAGGUGUGUGCAGGUCAGGAGGUGCCGUCCAGGUGUGCGGCGAGCCGCUGCGCACAGAUGUCAGGAUUUCCGUUUGGGUCUAGUUUAGAACCUGUCCUUAAACCUAGGGGUUGCUGUCAGGAUUUGCUUUCAGACUUUUUUUUUUUUUGUAAUUCCCUUUAGAGUCUACAAAAAUGUUUUUAAAAGGAUCAGGUCUGCUUUUAGUUUCAUUUUUGUUUCUUUCCCGUCCCACUCUUUAAAAACUGGUUCCGUGAGGAAAGGCAGAAGCCGUUCCGUGUCUCUUGCAGGCUGGGCCGGCUUCAUGCCAGUGCGAGGGCGUCCCGUGCCCACGUACAUACGUAUGUCUCCAUGAGUUCUGGGCUCCACUGGUUCCAAUUGAGCUCCAGCCCUGGUUUUCCUACCCAUGCAGUUAGGGACUUUAAUUUAAUUUUUUUUUUGUAGGGCCACCGCCUUCAAACACAACUGCUACAACAUUCUAAUAAAGGCUCAUUUAACCCCCAGGCUCCUGUCGUGUGAAUAUCCUCAGUCUGUAGGAAACUUUUUUUGACACAGCAUAGAAGACCUAGUUUUGGAAAACAUUAUCUAAUUUUUUGUUGUGCAAAUCCCCAAAUUUCUCACUAAUUUUUGUUUUUUUGUGCAUAACUUGGAUGGGCUGAAGGAGGUGAGGACAGAUUGGGGAAGGGUGGCUUUCAUUCCAAGAUCCAGGGAUUUGGGGAAAAGGAAGGAAUUUGAUGUUUUUUGGGGUGGGAGGGGAGGGUGUGUUUUUUACACCAAAAAAAAAAAAAAAAAUCAAGAGUAUGCAAGCAUUUCUAUUCCUCGCAUUUUUCUGUGUGCCUGGCAAAUAAAUACCUGUCUCCUACGACCCUGAGCUGUUAGCCCUCUCUGUUCCAUGACAGGGGCCAGAUCUUCCAGCUCCUCCCAGAAGGAGCACCCAGGCUGGCUUCUUCCCACUGAAAGCCCUCCCCAGCGAACCAACCUCAGUUCUAUGCAGUGGCUGGGGAUCAGGCAUCCAGACCGAAGUCACCUCUGCCUGCUCCAGCUUGGGUCAGCUGGGUCUGACCAGGGGGCCAGAUCCGAGCCGCACCUGCCGGCCCCCAGCCCCAGCUCCAGCUCCUGACCUCUCCCAGCCUGGCCUGGCUGUUCCUCCAGGGCUGAUGGCUGUCAACCCAUCCUUGUGAGUUCAUAUGGACUGCUGCCCCUCGAAAGGGAGAGGGUCGGCCCCAUGUCCCCAGGGAGCAUUCCAUCAGGGACAACGUACAUACUGUGAUGUAAACUUUUUUUUUUUCCCCCCAGGGGGCAAAAGUGUGAGAUGCCUUAAUCUUUCCUUCAUUUCUGCUGUCUCGAACACUCUAGCCCAUUAUUUCCUUUCAGUUCCUUGCAGCAUAACCUCUACGAUAAGCCCCAAGCGGGUUGUUGUAUUAUGACGUUUAUGAUGUUCCAGGUGAAGGCAUUAUUAAGUACCUCUCUGGGUGUGGGGUUUGGACGCACCAGGAUAGCUAUUGAUUAAUGUUAAGGGUGUUCUACCCACAGCAAAGCACACCCUCUUAAACCAGGCACUGCCUGGGUCCUGGUCCCGAGAGCCCUACCAGGAUCAGGUUCCUGCAAGCCGUCAGAAUGUGGGAGCCCCCAGCCCAACUGAUUGUAACUGUCCCCUGUUACCUGUGACAUGAACCUCCAACAGCACCUGGAAACGGUUCCCUCUGUCAGCUGCUCUGUAGACAGGGCUGGGGAGAUCUCAGAGUUCACACCUCGCCUGUUGUAGGGGAGGUUGGGGGUAGGGUUUGGAAUGGCCAAGUGCCCUUGGAACCUCCCACAGCUAUGGCCGUCCUGACCUCAUCCCAGGAACUCUACGGUGACCAGGAACCACCCCUCUGACGAGGUCUGUAGCGGCCCUUCUCAGAGUGGAACAGCCCACAGUGCUAGUUGUGCCUGGUCUUACCUGUACUCCACGGACCUCGGUGAAGCAAAAGCUUCAGGGCAGAGGGAAUGAGGCAACCCAGUGGCAGCCCCGCUGGGCCCCGUGGCUCCUGCUCUCCUAUUGGACGUAGAGGCAGGGGAGAGACUUCUCUAUACAAAUAUUCUCAUCACAGAAGGGAUGAUCCUUGCUGCUCUGCCGUAGGGUUUUUGAUGCUGAGCUAUGCUGCACAUGACGUUAACCUAAAGAACUUGGACUGAGCUUUUAAAAAAGGACAGCAAACAAUUUUAUAAUCCUUAAAGUGUAAUAGACGGUUACACUAGUGCAGGGUAUUGGGGAGGCUCUUUGGGUGUGGAGGCUGUCACUUGUAUUUAUUGUGACUCUAAAUCUUUGAUAGUAAAACAAAUGUAAAAAGAAAUGUUUGCCACCAGAUGGGAAUAGAAGUUCCAAUAAGCAGGCUGGAAUGGGUGGCUAUACGUUGUAUCACGAGGAAGUUUUAGACUCUGAAGGAUAAUAAAUGGAUGAUGUGUCAACUGGA